CAGAUUCUCUAAAGGCAUGCCUGGUGGCAUCACGUUUUUCACAUCUCCGCAUCUGGACCCUGCCCAAGCGAAGGCUGAUCUAGGCAGUCUCAUUGCUGGAGAUGACUGUCAGCUGCUUUCUCUGCAUAGCCACCAUCACAUGCCUCACCACUGGAGCCUGGGAAGCCUGACCACAAACCGGCAUCUCCAAGGCAUGAAUAAUUAGGUAGGCAUAAUGGAAGGCACUCAUUGUACCCUCCAAUUGCAUAAGCCCAUUACGGAACUCUGCUACAUCAGCUUCUGUCUUCCAAAGGGGGAAGUCAGAGGAUUUUCAUACAAGGGCACUGUAACUCUAGACAGAUCCAAUAAAGGUUUUCAUAACUGCUACCAAGUCAGGGAGGAGUCAGACAUCAUCAGCCUCAGCCAGGAGCCGGACGAACAUCCAGGCGACAUAUUUUUCAAGCAGACUCCCACGAAAGACAUUCUAACUGAGCUGUACAAACUCACAACAGAGAGGGAGAGACUGCUAACCAAUCUCCUGAGCUCAGACCACAUCCUGGGGAUCACGAUGGGGAACCAGGAGGGGAAGCUGCAAGAGCUGUCCGUGAGCCUGGCCCCCGAGGAUGACUGUUUCCAGAGUGCUGGUGACUGGCAGGGAGAGCUCCCCGUGGGCCCUCUCAAUAAGAGGAGCACCCACGGGAACAAAAAGCCUCGGAGGUCUAGUGGAAGGAGAGAGAGCUUUGGGGCCCUUCCACAGAAGAGGACCAAAAGAAAAGGGCGUGGAGGCCGAGAAUCAGCUCCUCUGAUGGGCAAGGACAAGAUCUGUUCCAGCCACUCCCUUCCUCUUUCUAGAACAAGGCCUAACCUUUGGGUACUAGAGGAGAAAGGAAAUCUGCUCCCGAAUGGGGCACUUGCCUGCUCCCUGCAGAGGAGAGAGAGCUGCCCCCCAGAUAUUCCCAAGACGCCAGACACAGACCUUGGCUUUGGGAGCUUUGAGACGGCUUUCAAGGACACUGGGCUUGGAAGAGAAGUGCUGCCCCCUGACUGCAGCUCCACAGAGGCAGGAGGGGAUGGCAUUCGGAGGCCGCCGAGCGGGCUGGAGCAUCAGCAAACAGGUUUGUCUGAAAGUCACCAGGACCCUGAGAAGCAUCCAGAGGCAGAAAAGGAUGAGAUGGAGAAGCCGGCUAAGCGGACUUGCAAGCAGAAACCUGUCUCCAAAGUGGUGGCCAAAGUUCAGGACCUGUCCUCCCAGGUACAAAGAGUAGUUAAAACGCAUUCUAAGGGUAAGGAGACGAUUGCCAUUCGCCCAGCAGCCCACGCUGAGUUUGUACCCAAAGCCGACUUGCUCACCCUCCCGGGAGCUGAGGCUGGGGCUCAUGGCUCCAGGCGGCAGGGCAAGGAGCGGCAAGGGGAUAGGUCAUCGCAGUCGCCAGCCGGGGAAACAGCCUCCAUUUCUAGUGUGUCGGCCAGUGCCGAGGGGGCCGUGAACAAGGUCCCCCUGAAGGUGAUAGAGAGUGAGAAGUUAGAUGAAGCCCCUGAGGGGAAAAGACUGGGCUUCCCUGUCCACACGAGUGUCCCUCACACUCGCCCAGAAACGAGAAACAAGAGGAGAGCCGGGUUGCCCCUUGGUGGCCACAAGUCCUUGUUUCUGGAUCUGCCCCACAAAGUAGGUCCUGACUCCUCACAACCCAGAGGUGAUAAGAAGAAGCCAUCCCCACCAGCACCGGCAGCUCUUGGCAAGGUGUUUAAUAAUUCAGCCUCGCAGUCCAGCACACACAAACAGACGUCACCUGUUCCCUCGCCUCUGUCUCCAAGGCUCCCCAGCCCUCAGCAGCAUCACAGGAUCCUCCGGCUCCCUGCAUUGCCUGGUGAGAGGGAAGCUGCUCUUAAUGACUCUCCUUGUAGAAAGAGCCGUGUCUUCUCUGGGUGCGUCUCUGCUGACACCUUGGAGCCACCAUCCUCUGCAAAGGUCACGGAGACCAAAGGAGCCAGCCCGGCCUUCCUCAGAGCAGGCCAACCUCGGUUGGUGCCUGGGGAAACUUUGGAAAAGAGCUUGGGGCCAGGGAAGACCACAGCUGAGCCCCAGCACCAGUCACCUCCAGGUAUCUCCUCUGAGGGCUUUCCCUGGGACGGCUUCAAUGAGCAGACACCUAAAGACCUUCCCAACAGAGAUGGAGGCGCGUGGGUUCUGGGCUACAGAGCGGGACCAGCCUGUCCAUUUUUGCUUCAUGAGGAAAGGGAGAAGUCAAACAGGAGCGAAUUGUACUUGGAUCUCCAUCCUGACCACAGCCUGACUGAGCAGGAUGACAGGACUCCUGGCAGACUUCAAGCUGUCUGGCCACCCCCAAAGACAAAAGACACAGAAGAAAAAGUGGGACUGAAGUACACUGAAGCAGAAUACCAAGCUGCUAUUUUACACUUGAAGAGGGAGCACAAAGAAGAAAUUGAAAACCUGCAGGCACAGUUUGAACUUCGGGCAUUUCAUAUCCGGGGCGAGCAUGCAAUGAUAACAGCGAGACUAGAAGAAACCAUUGAAAAUCUGAAACACGAGCUAGAACACAGAUGGCGAGGGGGUUGUGAAGAGAGGAAAGAUGUGUGCAUUUCCACCGAUGAUGACUGCCCUCCAAAGACCUUCAGAAAUGUGUGCGUCCAGACAGACAGAGAGACCUUCCUCAAGCCCUGUGAAAGUGAAAGCAAGACAACCAGAAGUAAUCAAUUAGUACCCAAAAAGCUGAAUAUCUCCUCUUUAAGCCAGCUCUCACCCCCAAAUGACCACAAAGACAUCCAUGCAGCACUCCAGCCAAUGGAGGGCAUGGCAUCAAAUCAGCAGAAGGCAUUGCCUCCGCCUCCCGCAUCCAUCCCUCCCCCUCCGCCCCUCCCCUCAGGACUUGGAUCUUUGUCUCCCGCACCUCCAAUGCCACCUGUGAGUGCUGGGCCACCGCUACCACCUCCGCCUCCUCCACCGCCACCUCUACCUCCACCUUCAAGUGCUGGACCUCCACCACCCCCACCCCCACCCCCACUUCCUAACUCCCCUGCCCCACCCAACCCUGGAGGGCCUCCUCCUGCUCCACCACCCCCAGGACUUGCACCCCCACCUCCCCCUGGACUCUUCUUUGGACUUGGCUCUUCUUCCAGUCAAUGUCCUCGAAAACCAGCCAUCGAGCCCAGUUGUCCCAUGAAGCCUUUAUAUUGGACUAGGAUACAAAUAAGUGAUAGGAGCCAAAAUGCUACACCAACCUUAUGGGACUCCUUAGAAGAACCUGACAUUCGGGACCCCAGUGAAUUUGAGUAUUUAUUCUCCAAAGACACAACUCAACAGAAGAAAAAACCUCUGUCAGAGACUUAUGAGAAGAAAAACAAGGUCAAAAAGAUCAUCAAAUUGUUGGAUGGAAAACGAUCUCAAACUGUGGGAAUCUUGAUAUCUAGUUUACAUUUAGAAAUGAAGGAUAUCCAACAGGCCAUUUUCAAUGUGGAUGACUCCGUGGUUGAUCUGGAGACCCUGGCAGCCUUAUAUGAAAACAGAGCCCAAGAGGAUGAGCUGGUUAAAAUAAGAAAGUAUUACGAGACAUCCAAAGAAGAAGAACUGAAGCUGCUGGAUAAACCUGAGCAAUUUUUACAUGAGUUAGCCCAGAUUCCUAAUUUUGCUGAACGUGCCCAGUGCAUAAUCUUCAGAUCUGUCUUUUCUGAGGGUAUCACCUCCUUGCACAGAAAGGUAGAGAUCAUCACGCGAGCUUCUAAGGACUUGCUGCACGUGAAGAGCGUGAAGGAUAUUUUAGCUCUCAUCUUGGCUUUUGGAAAUUAUAUGAAUGGAGGAAAUAGGACUCGGGGACAAGCCGAUGGAUAUAGCUUAGAAAUUCUGCCCAAACUCAAGGAUGUCAAAAGUCGGGAUAAUGGGAUUAAUCUGGUGGACUACGUUGUUAAGUAUUACCUGCGUUACUAUGAUCAGGAAGCUGGAACAGAAAAGAGUGUUUUCCCCUUGCCGGAACCACAGGAUUUCUUUCUGGCCUCCCAAGUCAAGUUUGAAGACCUCAUAAAAGAUUUGAGAAAACUGAAGAGGCAACUAGAAGUUAUCUUCAGGAUGCUACUAAAGAAAGUGCUGUCCCAUUAAAGAGGAAGACAUAGGUCACAGGAAAUAAAAAUUCAGUGGAGAAGGAAGGUGAAUGGAGCCUCCAGCACAGAGAAAAAGCCCAGGAUGGCAGCCAGACAUUGAAAGAAAACAUUUCAGAUUUGAUUAAGUCAAAAGCAUCAUGGAGAAGGUUCUUAAGGAAUACACAAUUAAUACAUCUAAUAUAUCUGAACGUUUGGACAAGAGAUUUUAUACAACUAGUAACAAGUGUGAGGUUCAUUUAACGUUAAGCUCAUAGAAAACAAACUAAAUCAGAAAAAAAAAUUCUGAGAGCAAGUGUGAGAGAAAGAGGAAAUGUGCGGGAAAUGUGGAAUAAUCAGAGUUUCCAUAUAUCAGCUGGGACUGCGAGUUGUUUUUGCAAAGUCAUAAUAAUGUCAACACCAAACGCUAGUCUAACCAAGUCAUGGUACCGUGUGCUAUAUUGGGGUGAUGGAAGUGAAGAGGCGGGAGUGAAGGAAAGAACUACAUCAUUUAUAGUUGAUAAAGAGAAAAAUAAAAAAAAAACAAUAGAAGCUUGUUAGAGACAUACUACUAAGCACCAAAUAAUCACAUAAAAUUGGUAAAAGAGGUAGCCUCUGAGGAGGAAGAAUUGAGGAAAUGGUGGGGUGGAGAUGGGGGACUGCUGUUCUUAAAGUGCAUAGAAUGUACUGAUUCUUUAAACUGCGUGCACGUAUAACUUUGACAAAUACAUAAAAACAAAAAAUCCCACAAUGAAACAAAGCAUUUGUGAAUUUGUUAAGUUUCAAUGACAGAGGCUGGUGUGUUGAAAAUAGUACUGAACUGAGAUUUAGGAGAUGUAAGUUUAAAGUUAAUUCUGCCUCUUAUCACAUGAUAAACCAUGCACUUUGCCACAUCACUUAGCCUCUGUGACUCUCAACUGAAAAAAAAAAUGGAGCCGAUCAUACUUCUGGAUUCUGCCCAACACAAAGGGAUAUUGAAAGGGUCAGAUGAGGCGAUGCCUGAGGAAGUACCUCAGGAGGUGUGAGGUAGUACUUAAAUUCCUGAGAGGCCUUGCAGUCUGCACUUUACUCAAUGGAUGCUGGUGUGUUCUAGAAGGGAGAGCAGGGUAUUGAUCAUUAGGACAGGUCUGGCUAAUUUAUCACCUUUUGGGAAGCUCCAGAAGACAUGACUUGAAUGAUUAUUGACCAUGUCUAAUUUAUUAGCUCUUUCCUCCUUCACAGCCCAUUUGUCCACAGCAGUAGUUUACUAAGUCUGAGCUCUGGUACGAGACUGGAUACAUUAGCCAGAGUCCUGACCAUGUUGCCAUGGUGUUAAAAAUAUUUAGUUUUGCAAGCAAAGUUUUAGAAAUAAUAAAAAAAACUUUGAUAUGAUUUAUUUUUGUAAAAUGAUUUCAACAAAACAGACCUAAGGAACUGGGAUAAGUAUUUCAGAAAAGCAGUGGGUGUAAAAUGUGGAUCGGCAUGGUGACUUUUGAUGCAAAGCAUUCAAUUAAUUGAGCAUGGUGACUAAAGGUCACACAUUUCCCAAAUGAAAUGCCUUCAAAGACAAGUUGUACAGAAAGGAGAGAGGAAACUGAAACUUGAUUCAUCCGUUUAAUUAAUGGAAGAAGUUUGUGUUUUCCUUUGAAGCUGUGAUUGUGACAUUUCUAGGUGGGAAGGAUGAGUUAUGUUGUCCUGGUUUCCUCCUCUCAGUUUGCACCCUCUAUUUCUACCCUCUAUUUUAUAAAAACACGUGGUUAAUAGAAUGUGUUUUGUUGAGUUUUUUUCUUUGACAAGAAACAUAAAAUAUUGAAAUAAAAGCUGCAAUCAUAGAAAAGUCUGGGUCAGAAGUCCUGAAUUCAAAUCCUUGCUUCACAAGCUUUGUAACCCUUGGCAAAUCAUUUCAUCCCUGACAUUUCAGUAUCCUCAUAUAAAAAUGAGUGUAAGGCUACCUGCUCCACUGAUUGUUUAAGAGGAUUUACUGGGAUCCCACAAAGGAAAUCCCUUUUCAUAGCAUAUGCCAAAUGUGUCAUACUUUUCCUUGAUUCCUUUUGUGCUCUCAUGUCUGACAGCUAGUCCUGUUGACUCUUAACUUCAAAAAGUGUCUGGAAUCAAUUCAUUGCUCUCCAUCUCCACACCUACUGCUUUUGUAAUCCAAGCUACCACCUUCUCACCUGGCCCAUAUCAAGCAGGUUUCUCUGCUUCCACUCUUGGUCUUCCUUUGUCUCCACCUGCCGCAUAGGUCACAGCACUCUGUUAUUUCAUCUUCAUUCCUCUUGGAAUCAAAUCCAACCUCAUACUCAUGCCGUACAAACUGAUUUAACCACUUCUGCCUUUCCAGUCUUCUCUCACACCACUCACCCCUCCUGCCCACUAAACUCCAGCCACACGGGCCUUCUUUGUGUUCCAACACGAUGUACUUGUUCCUGCUCUAGGAUCAUUGCAGUAGUGGGUCCCUCUCCUAGAAAGCCCUUCUGCCAGAUAGGCCCAUGCUCUGAGCCUUCCUUGCCCACCCACUCUUCAGGAGGCACUUUGAAUAGGCACUGUCUAUUACAGCCUUCGUUUUUCAUAUUACUUUCACAUAUUCAUAUUUCAUAUUAUUUUCUAUUUAUUUGUUUGUAAAUUUUCUCUUCCUCCACCAGCUUCAUGAAGGCAGAUAUAUGACCUUUUUUAUGUUUAUAUUUACUGUGCUGGUCAGCACUUUCCACGUAUUUGUUGUCAAUAUUUGGUAAAUGGGUGAAUGAAUGAGCAAAUGAACAAUGGAAGAAAUGACUCAACUUCAGAUAAUCGCUGACUCUGCUAUUAGUGAGAAAUUAGAUCACUUCCUUAUGGCCAAAGAUGUCAGAUAAGCAUCCGUGAGUAGAAUCUUUUAGAGGGACAGAUUUUAAAGCUGUCUGAAGAGAAAACUGAUGGCCUUGAGCAGUAGUGGGUUCCUCACCCACUGCUUGCUGGAAGAUUGUAUUAUGUGGGUGGGUAGAGGAGGUACCAUUAGACAAGUAGUUUGCUAGAUGAUUUUGAAGGUAUAUUCCAACUCCUGAAUUUCUGAGAUGAUUAUUCUUACUAUGCUAUUUCAGUGCAUUCUAUAAUUCUCCUUGUUCAUGAAGGGUUACUGUAUUGAAUUCCUCCCUAGACUGACUUAAUUAGAACAACUGAAAAAUCCUAGGAAUUCUGACCAUUUGCAAGACUUUUUUUUAAAAAGUCAACUUUCAAAUUAUAUCAGGCUUGCAUCUCAGGUAUUCUCUUUGUAAAUGACUCUGAACAAUCUCUUGAAUUAAUUCAUGCCUCAAAAAUUCUUGUGUUGAUACCAUCUAUCCUUUUUUUUUUUUUUCCUGAGACAGAAUAUUGUUCUGCCACCCAGGCUGGAGUGCAGUGGCACAAUCUCGGCUCACUGCAACUUCCGCCUCCCGGGUUCAAACGAUUCUCCUGCCUCAGCCUGCAAAGUAGCUGGGACUACAGGCACCCGCCAGCAUGCCCAGCUAAUUUUUUGUAUUUUUAGUAGAUACUGGUUUUCAUCAUAUUGGCCAAGCUGGUUUCAGACUCCUGACUUCAGGUGAUCCACCUGCCUUGGCAUCCCAAAGUGCUGGGAUUACAGGCAUGAGCCACCAUGCCCAGCCGAUACCAUCUGUCUUUAUAGAGCAGAGCGCUUAUCCAGUGUGGUAGGUUAAUGGAAAAAAAUUGGCCAAAAUUGGGAAUCAUGGAAAAUGACACUUGUAUCCCUUAACACUUUAACUUACAACAAAUUAAAUGUUGUAUCCUUUGUCUGUAUUCUGAUGCAGGGAUGAAGCUUUUACUUGAAUUAUGAAUCUGUCGAAUGCAGUCCUAUAGGUCUUCCCUACAUACUCCAUAAUGACAGCAUCUGUAAUUUCCCUACUGUAUUUUUAAAGUUCAGUAAAGACUCUUGCAAAUAUCACCAUAGAAUCUUUCUAGAUAUUUAUAAUUGUUCUCAAUCUUUUAAAACUGUGUUUCCCACACUUUUUAAACAAUACACUUUAAUUUUUAUUUUGGAAUAAUUUUUAAAUUGCAGAAAAGUUGCAAAGAGUAGAGAGUUCUCAUAUAGCUCUUCUCAGUUACUUUCCCCAUUCUUGGCAUCUCACACUGCUGUGAUCCAUUUGUUAAAACUGAGAAACUGGCAAUGAUACAUUUAGAUUGACUGAAUGCUAGUUUUUAUAUGGAUUUCACUGGUUUUUCCAUUUUUGUCCCCUUUCUGUUCCAGGACCUAAUCCUGACUACCACAUUGCAUUUAGUUGCCAUGUUUCCCCAGUUUCCCCUGGCCUUCUAUACCUACAUUUAACAGCAAUAUUUUAGCUUCUUUCAUUAAAACUUAUAGAAAUAGUACCUUUUGACAGUCAUAUAUCUGGUUUACCAUCAAGUCAUUAAAUUACAUAAUUUCAAUAAAAAGAACAACAGGAAUAAACAGGUUUAGAAACAACACAAGUGCUUUUGAUCAGGAUUCUGCUCGAUAGCUGGAAGACUGAAUCAAGUAUGAGGACUGGAAAAUAGCAUUAAUUUGGCAAGUUCAUUAACAAAGUAUCCUUGAUAUUUCCUGUUUUUUUGGUUUUUUAAAGGUACUCUUGUAAUUAUAAUGGUGAUACUUUACCUGCCUAUGGUGCUUCAUCCUCCCAAGUGAGUAGGGCAGGCAUAUGCAGCUUGGAAAACAGAGUCUUCGAGAUAGGAAGCAGCAUGGCCGGGAUCACCCAGCCAGGCACAGAACUCAGGUCCUUGACUGCCAAGCCAGCGCCCAAGCUACCAUACCAUGAGCUUGUAUUGGGUCAAAACAUUUUCUUUACAGAAAUAGAGUAGUGGAUAGUUUUGUGAAUAUCAAAAUACUUUUUCUGCCUAAGUAAGUUGUAUAUCUUUGACUCUGUGGAAGAUUCACAAUCCACAGAGAGAUUCUUCUCAUGUCAGUCAACCAAAUGAGUGAAGUUAGAGGGAGACCUCCUUAGCCCCUGCAAAGGGGACUGGAGUUUUUGCCAAUAUCCUUAUCUCUCGUAGAUUCUUUCCCAGAUAGCUCAACCUCAGCGUGGCUCCUAGGUGGAUAGGGGCCAUGAACUGUGACUCUACCUUUUAAUACUCCUGGAAAGAUCACAGACCUACCAGGAAAUUGACAGCCCUGGUUCCAGUCUCUGCCAUGCCACUUACUAACCUAACCACCUGGUAGGCCUUUUCCCCAUUUGAAAUGACAGGAUCCCAGUGGUGGCACUUGGUGAUUUUUUUAGCUUUUAUUAAUUCCUUACAGUUGACAAAGCAUUCACAUAGGUGUCCCAUAGUUUUUUCUAGAACUUUCCUGUAGAUGGUGAAAGUAGGAGGUGGCAUAUUAUAAGGGCAGGGGGUCUGUUACCCCUGGAUUCAGAUCCUGACUCAGCUACUUACUGUCUGUGUGACUUUACUAAUACUCACCAAAAAGGGGACAAUAGCAGGAAAACUUUCAUAGGGUAAGAUGAGAUAACACAUAAAGCAGGCUGAGGGCUAAGACACCCUUGGCCAUUUAAGGGCCAUUUGCUUUUGAUUAUACAGUUUGAAAAUUUGUUGUUGUUUUCAAGGAAUUACUGAGUGAGAGAUAAAUGGCAAUAUGUCCAAGUCAGCAUGGAGGACCAGGACCCGCUGGACCAGAAACUUUUCCUCUGCCAUAGUAAACAGAAAGGGGAAACGCCCAAGGAACAUUUAUAAUGGCUAAUGUACUAACAGUGCUAAUUUGGUUGUGUUUUUAAACCUUUUCUGGACCAUUUUGAUGGUCUUUAAAAAGUGUCAUCAAAUCUCCGGGUAUCAAAGAAAAAACUACAGAAUACGAGACAGAUCUUGUUUGACCUUUUCAAUCAAUUAAUUUGUUCAGCAAAUAUUUAUUCUUAGCACUGAGUUCACUGCGAAUUUUAAAUAAACUCACUGAAAGAUCAAGUCCUUUAUAAACACAUUUUAAGGGUAAGUUUUAUCCCCAUUUUCUAGGGGAGAGAUUUAUUCCUACUUCUGAUUUCUCUUCUGCUCAGGAACAGGAAUCUGACUGUACCUGAGAACAGAGAUAAUACUUGUCAGUCUGUUAGAGGGUAAACAGAGGGAAGGUAUAUAGAAUUUUCCCUCCAGCUGUUCUGAAGAUUCAUAAAAACAUCUGCAAAGCCCUUCCUGACUGUGAUCCUGAAGAGAAUCAACUAAUACUUGCCACCUUGGUUUCAAGGCAUUAUAUACCUUGGAAUUACAAACAUCUAAUUUUUUUUUCAAUCCAUGACAUACCUUUUCCUAACUCCACCAAAUCCCAAAGUUGAGUGUUUAAGCUGGGCUUGAUAUUCGCUAUAUAUAGCUAAUAUAGGCCGGGCUUGGUGGCUCACACCUGUAAUCCCAGCACUUUGGGAGGCCGAGGCAGGCAGAUCACGAGGUCAGGAGUUUGAGACCAGCCUGACCAACAUAGCGAAAUCCCGUCUCUACUAAAAGUACAAAAAAUUAGCUGGGCGUGGUGGCAGGCACCUGUAAUCCAAGCUACUCAGGAGGCUAAGGCAGGAGAAUCGCUUGAACCCAGGAGGCAGAGGUCACAGUGAGCCGAGAUCGCGCCAUUGCACUGCAGCCUGGUGACUGACAGUGCAAGACUCUGUAUCAAAAAAAAAAAAAAAAAAACAACUAAAAUAAAAUUGUGAAUCAUAACCAAUGGCGUAUUCAUUAAUGAAAUGGAGUAAAAAUAAAAAGGCGGCUAAUCUAGGAAUAAUUGAAUGAUGGAGCGGUUUUGCUGAGUCAUAUUACAUAUACCUGACUCAUCCCAAAGACAGAGACAAAUUCCUUGCGCUCCCCAGGCCAACAGGAGAUAGCUUGGAGGGGCCUCCAUGACUUUAAGUUUUAUCACCUAGUCUUAUUAACAUCAGGGCUGAAGAUGUUAGAGAGUUUAAUAGGCAUUUCAGAAUCUGUGACACCUAGCCUCUCAGUGGAUACUAUUUAUUUGUCAUUUCAGCCGUCUUGUUCUUCUCAACAUCAGCCCUGCCCAGAACUCCCCCUCUCCUCUAGCAGUCCCCCAUCCUUCCUCAGAUGCUUACACACACUCACUUUACGUAUAACCACGUAAUAGCCUCCUGUUAAAGGCUCCAGCAGCUCAUCAUCUCUAGCCUGACAGGCCCUAGGAUGCAGACUACCAGGGGCUGCUGGACCAGAAACUGUCCCUGCGCCAUAACUCAAGAGAGAGGUAGGAUCAAUGACAGAUUUACAGGAGAGCACAGUUUUAAAUAGCUGAGAUCAGUGUCUGGAGGCUUCCCGUUAAUACCACUAACGGCGUCCAGCAAGCGAGACUAUUGGCCACUUUGUUACCCACUCUAAACUGUUUCUGAUAUUCAACUCUAUUUUCAAACACAUCCUAAGAAAUCCCUACUCCCCCAAAAUUGACAAUGCAGCCUUCUUUAUAUGAAACCUUGUUUAUAGGCCACAAUUCUCCCGACAGAUUUACAAGUGUCUGUGGAGUUUUAAAAGACGAUUGCUUAACAGGCAUUAAGUGAGACACAUAGGACUGUGUAAAUAUUUUAGCUGGAAUAGGAUUUUUUUAAAUGUCUGAGCCAAAUAUUGCAUUAAAUCUGAAGACAGUGGCAAACUGAUUAGCAGUGGCUGCCAGCUCCAUGCUUUGCCAGUGAUUCUGGAGCCAAGACUAGAUACCAGAAUUCAUCCACCAGAUUAGGUUGUGUGUUUUAAAAAUAACUUUCCAUCCUUUUUUUUUUCCCUCUCUUCUCUUUAUGCCUUUCUGUCAUUUCUCCUUUAUUCCCUCAUGGUUCAUUUAGAUGUAAACACUUUCCAGAGUAGAAAAUUACAGUUAAUGUGACUAACCAGCGAGGGCUGAAACGGGAACAUGGGCUCAGAGGUCAGAGAAACCGUGGAAGACUUGCAGCUGUCCUGGUGGAGCAAUGUGGGGACAGGUUGCUUUUUACUAAUAGGCCUUGUGUAUCUUAAUCACUGGCCUCUUUGUAGCCAGCUGUUGCACUGCUGGAAGGGGACUAGUCCUAAGACCAGCAUUGCUGUAAUACCUCUUCCUCUUACUGAUUUCCUUGAUUCAUAAAGAGGCUCAGGCCUGUGGCCUUCAAGACGUGUAUGUGUGAGAGAAUCCUCAAUUCUAGUAAAAAUUGCCACAAAAUAUGCAUUUUGACUUCAGAGGACAUAUUUAGUAUUUAAGCAUUCCUAUAGGAGUACUAUUUUCCUGAUUAGAGCAGUGGAUAAGAUGUGUUGCUAUAAUUUUGGGAGGAGUGAGGCGUUCUAGCUAACAACUUUGCUCUGCCUUUGCUGACUUUUAACCAUUGUCUUGCACUAAUGAUACCUGUAUGCUUCUUGAAGUACUAUUCAAUGGGAGUGCCCCAAAAUAUAGGCUCUAUAUGUUCUUCACAAAUGACUUGAAUUGCAAUCGUAUGUCCAAAUGAUUACUUGAUAUUGUUGAUUGGAAAGUCUGAGCAUUUAAAAUUUUGUGUGCUCAUAAUUAUAUAAAUGUAUAUUACAAAACUCUGAGUGUUUGAUGUAAGUUUGCUGUACACUUCCCCCAAGUUCAGACAGCUUUGCUAGUGCUGACAGUAGCAUAAUUUACAUUCCAAUUAAACGUGACACAUUAGGGCCUUUCAAAAAAAAAAAAAAGAGCUACUUUCAUGCACAGGCCUCAAACCUAGUUUUAUGCUGUGAUUAAUCCCCAAUUUCUAUAUCAACUCUCAUAUAUCACCAGUUAUGGUCUUGUGUUUGAGUAAAUUACUUCAGUGGAUGGAUGGUCCUCUUACUGUUUUCCAUUCCAGAGUUUUGCACUUCCAAUGUGAUGACCGUAGUCCCUACAUGACAGUGACAGGCACCGUUCUAGCUUGCAUGGAGCCAGCCACCUCUGCAGAGUGGUACAGAAAAUGGUUUUAUUUCCAAAAUCUCUCCCCUUCAUCUCUCCCAUUGUGGUACAACCCAUUUUGUACCAAAAACAGUUUGACCACUAAUAUCAAGAAUUCUACAAAGGUUUUUCCUUUUUACCUAUAAUUUCAUUUCUUGUAUCUUUUAUCUUUGUAUCUUGUAUCUUUAGGUCAUUUCCUAAAGAAAUGACCCUCAACCUAGAAUAAGUUUGUAUGGACACAGAUGUGGCUCAAGCCUGACUCCCCAUGAGAAUAAGGUAGAAAGGAUUUCACUAUCCAACUACAGGAGAAUUAAGUGAGCUAUGGCAUGCCUACCUGAUGAAAUUUUAUAUGGCUGUUAAACAUGCUUGUGGAGUUUGUGAAAUAACAGGAGAAUGUGUGCAUGAUAUGUUAAUAGAAAGAAUCAAAAUACAAAAAAAUUCUUUAUCAAAUAUAAGUAAGGCAACCCCCAUAAAAUGAUGGAGGGGCAAGGAGCGCGAUACCGAGGCCCAGACCCUGAAAGAGAAAGUAUGCAAGUCUUAGAUGGUGACUGUGUUUUGGUCAUGGUGUCAUGACCGAUUUGUUUUUUCUGCUGUUUUAAAAAUGUUUUUCAAAUGUCUUUGUGUGUAUAUGUUACCUUCCUAAUACUUUUUAGAAGUUAGUCGCUGCUCUCCUCCCGAAGAUGAGUUCCCUUCCCCUUCAGAGGCCCGGUACCUCCAUGCCUGGGCUGCCUGCCUAGGACCCCUGCCACACAGUCCACCUCGAUGCCAGAGCUUGCAGUAUGUGCCUUUUUCUUCCAUGUUAACACAACUUUCCUACCUAUUGUUUUUGAAAUCCCCUACCUCCUAAACCAAUCUUAGAAAUACAUUUCUACUAAAGCAUUAAAUUAUUCUUGACAAUGUUUUCUUUUUCAACGAAUACAUAUGCAUUUCUAAUGAAAUUUCUGGAGUUACCAUCUUUAAUUCAAGGGAAGGCUUCUCAUGGUGGCGAUUUUUGUGGGGACCAGUGAAAGGGAUGUUUUUGAAUAAAUGUUUGAAUCGCUUAACACCCUAUAAAUCAAAUCAUGCCCAAUCCAUCUAUAUUUAGGCCUCGUCAUGGGUAGGUGAUUAAUGAAUAUGUUUCAUGCUAAUGUCUCGCAGACCGAGGCUGCGUCCGUAACCACAUAAUCAUCACAGUGGAAAUUCUGACUCAGCUGUGACGUUUGGUAGGCGGGACCUUUGAAUGGUGCUUUAGACAAUUCCGUGCAAAGGCUGUAGUCAGUGGCCCAGCUUUGCAAGUCUUUCCAAAAGUCCUAAAGCGCACUAGCAUGUCCUCACUUGGCCCUGUCACCUCUGCUUAAAUUUUUUCAUGGAGAAUACUCACUCCCAAUCAUGGUACAUUAAGGUGAAUUUGAUCUUGGGCAGCCUCCCUCAGUGGAGUGAAUCAGAAUCAUGGGAUUCCCCUGGACUCCAGCUUCCUGGUGGGUUUAUUUUUAUGGAACAUUCCUCUGGAGAAAGAGGCAGCCGCUCUGUAAAGGGCUAGACCUCUUCUGCACGUGAUCAAAGUAGCCCUAGAGAAUAUCUUCUUGUAUGGAAUGAUUUUUAUGACAUGAUGGCUUUGGGAGUUUUCUUGAAAAAUUAAAGGAAGAAUCUUUCUAAGGAGUCCUACUACCAUGAAAGGAAACUAUCAAAAACAUCCCAGGCAGAUAAGAACUAAAUCAGUUUUAAAGUCACCAAGAAAACAACACUUCCAUGGCCUCAUUUGAUCUUUAGCACUUGACCAGGAAAACUAGAGCUAUCUUUUAGGCUUAAUUCCAACGACUUCCCCAUUUUGGCGUUCUUUCUGUAGCUUAACUUCUUAAACAAGUGGCUACAGAAUCUUUCUCCAUUUACCUCACGCCUCUCCAAGCUGGCUUUUUCCCCGCACCCCCAACUUCCCUGGAACUGCUUUUGAGAUUACAAGUGACCUCUGUGUCACUAGAAUCAGUGUUAUUUCUCUGUCUUCAUCUCACUUGAUCCUUCUGCACAGAGCUGACUGCUCUUUCUUUCCUGCAAUUCUGUUUUCUUCUCAGGUCAUGUAACUCCAGACCUUCACUUUCCUACUGACCAGCUCUUCUCUGUUCAUUGCUGGCCUCUCCUCCACUGUGCACAUGCCCCAGGGUUUGUCCUGCAACACCUUCUCUUCCUUGGCUGUAUUCUCCCCAUGGCAAUUCAUAUUUUGCUAUCACUUUAAAUACCAAUUUUAUACCAAUGACUUCCUGGCAUGUGUGUCUACUCCAGCCAUGAGUCCCAGACUGCAGACUUUUAUAUAUACUUGAGUGUCUAAUUCACAUUUCAAACUUAAUGUGCUCUAAAUAACACCUUUGAUUUUCCACCUCGAGCUUGCUCAUGACUCCCUCCCUUACUCUGAUUAAAUCUCUAGUCAAAUAGCUUCACAGUGAGACUUUUCCUAACUACUUUAAGUAAAAUUGCAAGCCCCUUAUGUCUGUGACACUUUUCCUAACCAGGCUGGUCACCAGCCUUUUCACCGUUCACCUGAGUGUGUAACCUGGGAUACCUUUGGGGCCCAGAAGCUUUUCUCCCCUACGCACACUCUUUCCUUUACACCAAAAUCUGAAUGCAGAACACCAGUGAUCUGAGGAGAGAAGGUCCCACAGCUCCAGACAUGCUACACCACUUAACUCAUUCAAAUGGCCCGUGCGUUCUCAUCAUGUAUUACUUUUAUUCAUGACAUUUCACCUUAAUUCUCUUUCCUCACUGUGGUUGAGGGCUAGCUCCUCCUUGACCUUUGCAGUUCAACUCAUAAGUUUUCUCUCCUGGAGAGCCUUUCCUGGCUACUAACUCCUGGCCCAGUCUGAAAUAGAGGCCUAUACCCAGCGUUCCAUCACACCACACUAUAU